GUACGCAGAGGCGGUAGUGACACAGGCACAACUGACAGUGGCAGAAGCUCAGCUGACAAGGACUGGGGACGGCGGUGUCCUUGUCUUGCCUUUGUCGCCCCCGCCCCUCUCUUCCCUGGCUGGACUUGCGGAGUCCCCGCCGAAGAACCCGAGGGUCCCCUGGCGAUGGCAGAAAUGAACCCUGCACAGGGUCAUGUGGUUUUUGAAGACGUGGCCAUAUAUUUCUCCCAGGAGGAGUGGGGGCAUCUCGAUGAGGCUCAGAGAUUGCUGUACCGUGAUGUGAUGCUGGAGAAUUUGGCCCUUUUGUCCUCACUAGGUUGUUGCCAUGGAGCUGAGGAUGAGGAGGCACCUUUAGAGCCAGGUGUUUCUGUAGGAGUGUCACAGGUCAUGGCUCCAAAGCCCUGUCUAUCUACCCAGAAUACCCAGCCCUGUGAGACAUGUAGCUCACUUCUGAAGGACAUUCUGCGUCUGGCUGAGCAUGACGGAACACACCCCGAGCAGGGACUGUACACGUGUCCAGCACAUCUUCACCAGCACCAAAAGGAGCAGAUUAGAGAGAAACUUUCUAGAGGGGAUGGAGGAAGACCGACAUUUGUGAAGAACCACAGAGUUCACAUGGCAGGGAAGACCUUCUUGUGCAGUGAAUGUGGGAAAGCCUUUAGCCACAAACAUAAACUUUCUGACCAUCAGAAAAUCCACACUGGAGAAAGAACUUAUAAGUGCAGCAAAUGUGGGAUAUUGUUUAUGGAAAGGUCCACACUCAAUAGACAUCAGAGAACUCACACUGGAGAAAGGCCUUAUGAGUGCAAUGAAUGUGGGAAAGCCUUUCUUUGUAAGUCUCACCUUGUUCGUCACCAGACAAUCCACUCUGGAGAAAGGCCUUAUGAGUGCAGUGAAUGUGGGAAAUUGUUUAUGUGGAGUUCCACACUCAUUACACAUCAGAGGGUUCACACUGGAAAGAGGCCUUAUGGUUGCAGUGAAUGUGGGAAGUUCUUUAAGUGCAACUCAAACCUCUUUAGGCAUUACAGAAUUCAUACAGGAAAAAGGUCUUAUGGUUGCAGUGAAUGUGGGAAAUUCUUUAUGGAAAGGUCUACACUCAGUAGACAUCAGAGAGUUCACACUGGAGAAAGGCCUUAUGAGUGCAAUGAAUGUGGGAAAUUCUUCAGCUUGAAAUCCGUCCUCAUUCAACACCAAAGAGUUCACACUGGAGAACGGCCUUAUGAAUGCAGUGAGUGUGGGAAGGCCUUCCUUACAAAGUCCCACCUCAUUUGUCAUCAGACAGUUCACACUGCAGCAAAGCAGUGCAGUGAAUGUGGGAAAUUCUUUAGGUAUAACUCUACACUUCUCAGACAUCAGAAAGUCCACACUGGAUAAGGCCCUUAUGAAUGCAGUGGAUAUGGGAAAGCCUUCAGUCACCAACAUAUUGUGGCUGGACAGCAGGCAGUACACACUGGAGAAAGACUGAAUGCCGUGAACGUGGGUAAUUAUGUAGGUACAGCUCUCCAGUCGCUAUGUAUCAGAGAAUUCACACUGCAGAAAUGUGUGUUCAGCAAACUCGGGACAUUAUUUUGGUUUGACUCUCAUCUCAUUAGACAUUGGAGAGUUUACACUGAAGAAGAGUCUUUUCAAUAAAGUAGAAAGUGGUAAAGAUUCAACAUGCAAGAUUGUACUUAUUGGGCUUCAGAAUAUCCACACUAGUGAAAGUCUUCUGAGUACAGCAAAUGUGUGACAUUAUUUUGCUACUACUCCACACUACUUAGACAUCAUGUAGUUCACACUGGAAAAAGGCCACGUAUGUGCCUUGAAUGUAGCCAAAAUGACGAACAACACCCAGAAAUCUGUGAUUUAGCACUGAGAACUAGUAUUAUAUGGUUUUUAAAAAACAAUGGUGAAGUACAUGCCACAUAAAAUUUGCCAUCUUAACUAUUGUAAUGUCUUGUUUAAUACUUGAAGUACAUUAACAUUGUUGAGCAAAGAAUAUCCUGAACUCUUUAUCUUGUAAAAUGAAACUCUAUAACCACCAUUAAAAAAACAACUCAUUCCCACAUUCUUCAGUCCCUGGCGACCACCAUAUUUUUAAGUCAUUAUGACUCUGACUAUUCUUGGUACUUCUCAGAAGAAGAAUCUUAGAGUGUUUUUCAUUAUUUUUUUUCACUUAGGAUAAUAUCCUCAAAGUUCAUUCAUUUUUUAGCAUGUGUCAGAAAUUUUAAGGCUGAGCAAUAUUUCAUUGUUUGCAUUUACCACAUUUCCUUUAUUUCUGACAUCUAUUCAUGGACACUUGGGUUACUUCUACCUCUGGCUAUUGUGAAUAUUGCUACUACAAGCAUAAGGGCACAAAUAUCUCUUUGAGACCCUGCUUUCAAUUCUUAUUGGGUACCCCAAAAAGUGGAACUGCUGGAUCACAUGGUACUUCUAACUUUAAUUCUUUGAUGAACUGAGAAACUUUUCCAUAAAACUUGCACCGUUUUACAUUCCUAACAUUCCACAAAAGUUGUGAUUUGUCCUCAUUCUAAUCCAUAGAAGGCAACAUUUCUAACAGGUUUCUAGGUGAUUUUGUUGUUGCUGAUGUAGGGACUACAUUUUGAGAACUGUCCUAUCCCAUUUUUAUAACAAUGCAGAGCUUCUCUGUAAAUACCCCUUGUUUCUAUGUUCUAUCCUGUGAGCCUUUUCAUUUUGUUAAUUUUUCCCAGUGUUUACAACCAGGAAAUAGCUUGUCAUCUUUGAUACAAAACAGAAAUCUUUGCAAAAUACCAA